GCCAUCUUGCGUACGGAGGUGAGGUUUGUUACCGCGAUUCUGAGAGGUGGGCUUUUAGUCCCUCCAGACCUCGGCUUUAGUGCUGUCUCCGCUUUUCUUUCACCUUCACAGAGAUGUCUUAUGGUGAAAUUGAAGGUAAAUUCUUGGGACCUAGAGAAGAAGUAACGAGUGAGCCACGCUGUAAAAAAUUGAAGUCAACCACAGAGUCGUAUGUUUUUCACAAUCAUAGUAAUGCUGAUUUUCACAGAAUCCAAGAGAAAACUGGAAAUGAUUGGGUCCCUGUGACCAUCAUUGAUGUCAGAGGACAUAGUUAUUUGCAGGAGAACAAAAUCAAAACUACAGAUUUGCAUAGACCUUUGCAUGAUGAGAUGCCUGGUAAUAGACCAGAUGUUAUUGAAUCCAUUGAUUCACAGGUUUUACAGGAAGCACGUCCUCCAUUAGUAUCCGCAGACGAUGAGAUAUAUAGCACAAGUAAAGCAUUUAUAGGACCCAUUUACAAACCCCCUGAGAAAAAGAAACGUAAUGAAGGGAGGAAUGAGGCACAUGUUCUAAAUGGUAUAAAUGACAGAGGAGGACAAAAAGAGAAACAGAAAUUUAACUCUGAAAAAUCAGAGAUUGACAAUGAAUUAUUCCAGUUUUACAAAGAAAUUGAAGAGCUUGAAAAGGAAAAAGAUGGUUUUGAGAACAGUUGUAAAGAAUCUGAACCUUCUCAGGAACAAUUUGUUCCAUUUUAUGAGGGUCAUAAUAAUGGUCUCUUAAAACCUGAUGAAGAAAAGAAAGAUCUUAGUAAUAAAGCUAUGCCAUCACAUUGUGAUUAUCAGCAGAACUUGGGGAAUGAGCCAGACAAAUAUCCCUGUAAUGGACAAGUAAUACCUACAUUUUGUGACACUUCAUUUACUUCUUUCAGGCCUGAAUGGCAGUCAGUAUAUCCUUUUAUAGUGCCCUAUGGUCCCCCUCUUCCCAGUUUGAACUAUCAUUUAAACAUUCAGAGAUUCAGUGGUCCACCAAAUCCACCAUCAAAUAUUUUCCAAGCCCAAGAUGACUCUCAGAUACAAAAUGGAUAUUAUGUAAAUAAUUGUCAUGUUAACUGGAAUUGCAUGACUUUUGAUCAGAACAAUGAAUAUACUGACUGUAGUGAGAAUAGGAGUAGUGUUCAUCCCUCUGGAAAUGGCUGCAGUAUGCAAGAUCGAUAUGUGAGUAAUGGUUUCUGUGAAGUCAGAGAAAGAUGCUGGAAAGAUCAUUGUAUGGACAAGCAUAAUGGAACAGACAGGUUUGUGAACCAGCAGUUUCAAGAGGAAAAGUUAAAUAAAUUGCAGAAGUUACUUAUUCUUUUAAGAGGUCUGCCUGGUUCUGGGAAAACAACAUUGUCUCGAAUUCUGCUUGGUCAGAAUCGUGAUGGCAUUGUGUUCAGCACUGAUGACUAUUUUCACCAUCAAGAUGGGUACAGGUAUAAUGUUAAUCAACUUGGUGAUGCCCAUGACUGGAACCAGAACAGAGCAAAACAAGCUAUCGAUCAGGGAAGAUCUCCAGUUAUAAUAGAUAACACUAAUAUACAAGCUUGGGAAAUGAAGCCAUAUGUGGAAGUGGCCAUAGGAAAAGGAUACAGAGUAGAGUUUCAUGAACCUGAAACUUGGUGGAAAUUUGAUCCUGAAGAAUUAGAAAAGAGGAAUAAACAUGGUGUGUCUCGAAAGAAGAUUGCUCAGAUGUUGGAUCGUUAUGAAUAUCAAAUGUCCAUUUCUAUUGUAAUGAAUUCAGUGGAACCAUCACACAAAAGCACACAAAGACCUCCUCCUCCACAGGGGAGACAGAGACGGAGUCUCGCUCUGUUGCCCAGGCUGGAGUCCAGUGGCGCGAUCUUGGCUCACUGCAAGCUCUGCCUCCCGGGUUCACGCCAUUCUCCUGCCUCAGCCUCCUGAGUAGCUGGGACUACAGGCGCCCGCCACCAUGCCCGGGUAAUUUUUUUGUGUUUUUAAUAGAGACGGGGUUUCACCUUGUUAGCCAGGAUGGUGUUGAUCUCCUGACCUCGUGAUCCACCCGCCUCGGCCUCCCAAAGUGCUGGGAUUACUGGCAUGAGCCACUGCGCCUGGCCAGAAAUUCUUAAUGUAUUAUCACUCUAUGCACAAGAACAAGAAGAAGGAGUAGCACAAAUAACUUUGGAAAGAGAGUCUCAACAGUAAAUAGUUAUUCUAGAAGCUAAGCUGUAUGUAUUGAAAAGUUUUGACUUUUUGUAUAUCCAAUAGAAAUUUAUUUAAUCAUUCAUAAUCUCUUUUUCUUCCUUCUCCUUCUGACAAAUUCUGUUCUCUGAAAAAUAACCCUGUUACAUUCCAGUUGUGGUAAUUGUAAUAAUUACACAUUAUAAUUCACUUCCCAGAAUGGAAUAUGUUAACUUCAGUAAGUUCUCUUAAAUUUCAGUGUGGAAAAAAAUAGAUGAUUUUUCUGUAGGAUGGACACAGGCACAGUCUGAUCCCUAAUCUCAAAACUAGACACAAUUGCAUUAGCAAUUGGUGAGUAACUGAAGACUUCACAUUGAAGUCUUGGUUUGGUUUUUAAUAUUUCCAUUUCCUUUUUUUUUGUAAUUGAACUACUUUUUGUAAAUUAAUGGGAAGAUUGAAAUACUUUGAGAGGAGCUAUUGGGUUUGCCUCUCAGUUUUGCUAGUAACUAAGGGAAAAAGAAUAAUGUGGUUUUUCAUGGUUGAAAUUGUGUUUUAGUAGAGUCCAUUGAAAUAUACUUUAUUAUUUGGAUUAUUUUCUUAUUUUCCAGUUUUAACUGUUUUCAGAUGGUACAUGUAAAGUUAAAGUUUUAUUCUUGGUGUUAAUUUUCAGUUGGUAAUUAUAAUAAUUAUACAGCUUUCAGAAUAUCUCUUCAUUCUGAAAGAAAUUCUGAAGAGUAAUUCUGAACUCUUCAGUUUUUUAGUGUAACAAAAUGAAAGAAAAUUUACUCAGGAAGGGAUUGUGGGUUCUUUGUUUUCCUUUUUUUUUCUUCCGUUUUUCUUAAUCUUAGAAAUCAUAUUUCUUUUUCUUUCAUAGUCUUUUCUUGUGUACGUGUUUUCUUUCACUCUAUUCAUUUUUUGCUCAGCUAUCCUCCUGUAACCUCAUAACAUUCUUAAUGAAGAUGAUGGGAUGGUAAGUGUCUGGCAAAGCGGGAGAUAAUAUCUUUUUCCCUCCUGUAUUCUACUGAACUCAUUGUUCCUUCUCAGCCUUACUUAAUCAAGUUAAACUUAUACACCACAGCUCUGCAUUUAGUUUCCUGACCCUGUGGGUUAGGUAGAAUUUAGAUACGAAAAUGGCUGGAAAGAUUUAUAAAAAUCUAUUAUGUUAAUCAUUGGUGGGGAAUCCAUAACAUGGCAUAGAACUUGAAUGUAUGGAUUUGAGAAAAAAUAUUUACAUUAACUUAAUUAUAUGAUGAUGGAUGCUAAUUGAUAAGCAGUAGGUUGAAAUUCACUGUUACAUAAUUCACUAUUAUGUCAUGGUUGCUGGUUGCCCUUAACUGAAUGAUUUUGAAGGAAAGCUGAUAACUAUUUUGAGUUAAAUUUUUACAAGUGGUUCCUUAUAUGGUGCAAUGCCGCUGCAACAAACAGUAGGAAUUUUGUAGCAAAAAGUCUUAAUAGUAUCCAUUUAAAUAACUGCUGCUUAUUUAAUGCCCAUCAGUGCUAGGCCCCCAUCUAAAUGUGAUUGUUACAGUCAUUAAUUUUCACAAUUCUACAAUGGCUUUAGAAAGAGGAAACAAAAAUUUAGGUUAAACGACUUACCUAACAUGAUUUCUCUAGUAAGAGAUAAAACUGUGAUUCAAAUCUAUGUUAGACAUGUAUCUACUGUAACCCUGUAUUAUUUUUUUUUAACCACAUAGUUAUCUUUUUUUUUUUUAAUUUGGUGUUUUUCCAAGGUUAAAAAGAAAUUCCAGUGAAGAGUUGAUUCCAUCUUUAUGGUAUCUUUAUUUUUUAAGGUUAUAAGGUAUGUUGAUUUAUCAGGAAAGUUAAAUGAAGAAAUCUUCAAGAGGCCAUUUAUAAUUCUGUUUUUAAAAGUCAAAAUUGAAAAGAGUUGGGCCAGGUGCAGUGGCUCACGCCUGUAAUCCCAGCAUUUUCGGAGGCCGGGUGGGUAGAUCACCUGAGGUGAGGCGUUGGAGACCAGCCUGGCCAACGUGGUGAAACCCUGUCUUUACUAAAGAUACAAAAAUUAGCUGGGCGUGGUGGCAUGUGCCUGUAAUCCUAGCUACUCAGGAGGCUGAGGUAGGAGAAUCGCUUGAACCUGGGUGGCAGAGGUUGCAGUGAGCCAAGAUGGUGCCAUGCACUCCAGCCUGAGCAACAGAGUGAGACUCCAUCUCAAAAAAAAAAAAAAAAAAAAUUGAUAGAGUUUAUACUAUUUAAUGUUUAAAUGUUUUCUGUAAAUUAAACAUCAAUAGACUUGAUAAUCAUAUUUUAGGAACAUUUUUUUCCAUUGAAUUAUUUACAUAUACUGUUGUACUGUAAGGCUUUAAAUUAAUUUUAAUAUUUUAUUAUUUUAAUUAGCAUUUGAAAUGUAUAGUGUUCAAUAAAUGGAUUGCUAAAUUAUGUUAAGUUGGAUUUUUUUAACCCUAAUUAAUUUUCAGGCAGUAUUUCCUAAAAUAAGUCAAUACUACUUGUAAGUGGUUUUACUUACUUUUCUUUUAUGUCCACUUGUUACGUAAGUAUGUUAGUAGUAGACAUCAUGGAAAUUACAUAAAUUUUCCGAAUAUUUGAAGAAUUAAAGGAGCUUUUUCUCUAUAAUAGGAACUUUUUAUUCUUUUAUGGAAUUUUAAAUUAAUUUUCUGAAAGAACAGUAAAAGAGACAGUUACUUAAGUUUGCUUUGUAAAUAACUUAAAUUUUACAAGGAAAAUCUUGAAGUACAGAAUUCUUACUGUUGGGUAUUUGCUUUAUUUUGUUUUAGUCAACUUAAAAAAAUUGAAGAACUGGGUCUUGUUUGGUUUCUCUUAAUUCCUUAAGAGUAGUUUGUGUUUUUUCUUCAUUGUUCUAAAUGUUAGAGUUGGAGUUUUUGUUUAGAAUAGAAAAGUUGGAAUUUUUGUUUAGAAAAGAAAUGUCAUUGGUUUUAUGAAUAGAUUAAGAUAGUUUUCAAUUCAGGAAACUGGUAAGCAGUACAUAAGGGUAUUGAGAUUAUAGGAAUAUAGUUCAAUGUAACCCUUGGCAGAGAUGCAGUUAAGACAUUUAUCUAGAAUAUAAGUAAAUUGAAGUAUUUAUAGGAAAUGUGAUAAGAGUAAUGGGCUAGACAUUUUGAAAAUUAAAACCAGGGAUCUUGUUAUCUUUGGAUCACUACUGUGUCCUAGGAGCUUUAUUCUUUACUAAGAAUCAGUAACUGUUUUAUUCGAUAUUAGGCACAGUCUUCUCCCUAAAACAGUCAACAAACUUUUGAUACGAAGGAAGCAGUAAUCAAAGAAGAGCAACGUUACAGGGCAGUUUGUAAUAAAAGUUGAGUACCCCUAUCUGAAAUGCUUGAGACCAGAAGUGUUUUGGAGUUCAGAUUUUCUUUUGGAUUUUGGAAUAUUUGCAGAAUACCUACUGAUUGAGCAUAUCUAACCUGGAAAUCCAAAGUGCUCCGGUGAACAUUUUCUUUGAGCAUCAUGUCAAUCAAUGCUCAAAAAGUUCAGGAUUUUGGAGCUUCUUGGAUUAUGGGUGCUCAACCUGUAUAGGAAACGUGGAGAUGGAGCAUGAAUCAGUUGUAUUUGAUACUUGCUGGGGAAAGGAUUUCCAGACCACCAGAGAAGAAGGAUCACCCAUUUAACUUGGUGUAUCCAGUGCCAUAUCAGAGCCUUUUCUUCCAUUUUAACCUCACCAGUAGUCUUUAGAUUUGUGGUUUAUGAUCAAGAAAUUAAAUCCUAGAAUACAGAUUAGUAGAGCAAAGUUGAGGCUUUUGAUUAUCUAUUUCUUUUAAGGUUUUUCGCUUUAACACUUUACAGAAGAAUUUCUAGACUGUCUGAGAAGAAUACUCCAGGUAUUUGUCCCAGUCUUAAAAUGGUUCAACAAAAAGUUCAUAAUCACUUUUUAGAACCCUUUUCCCAAAGAACUGUGAUCCUACGUGUAACUUAAAAAAAGAAAACACACAAAUGCUUGCAUCUUUUUUCACAUAUUUAUCUGUAUUCAGCAAUCAAGAAUAGCUGGUACUGAUGGAUAUCUUUACAUGAUUUUUCGUUAUUUAUCUGAAAAUAAUAUAUAUUGGGUCAUUAUUUGGCUUUUCAACCUCAGUAAUUCAGUAACUUUCUUUCAGUUAAUUUUGUUGACCUGUUUUGGACACUUUUCAAAAUAUUCUUAGCAUGAUUUUACUGGGAAGAACACAUUAUUACAAGAGUUAGGCAGUCUGAGUUCCACCUCCAUUUGUGUCCAUCCUCUCUCGUUUGUUUAUUGAAUGCCUUCACCUGUGCUCUGAAUUGCAUCUCUUUCCUUCUCAGGAAAUUUUAUACAUUGUCAAUUAUUCCUUCUCUCUAACUUCAACCUCGCCUUCUUUGCUGAGUCUGACCCAUCAACAGUUAAACAUGAUCAAGUCUUCCGAUUUAAAAGUCCCUCUUUCUUGACACAGCUCAUUUAUAGCCAAACUUCUUUCUGAAGAGUAGUCUACAUUCAUUUUCUUUUUCUCCCUCACUUCUGAUAAUAUUGAACCAACUCCAUUUUAGUUUCUGUCCCUAUCAUUCCUCUAAAUUGAUUAAGGUCUCCAGAAUAUUCCUCUGUAUUUACGGGCAUUAUUCACUGCUCUUCUUAUUUGACUACUCAGCAAGCAUUUAACUUUUGAUCAGUUUUUCCUUAAAAUACUUUACUUGGCUUCCUUGACAUCAUGGUUUUUGUUCAGAUCUCUGUGGUUAUUUCUGUCUCCUUUGCUGCCUUCUCCUCUUGGUCCUUGAAUUUUAGAAUUCUUCAAAUUUCAGUUCUAGACAAUCUUCUGUUCUUACUCUUAGCUUUCCCUAUGUGGUCUCAUCAUUUCUCAUGUGGACAUAGUAGUCUCCCCACUUUUAUUUUUGCCACCUUACAAUUUUAUCCACAGAGCAGCUAGAGUAGUCUAUAAAUUCUUUUUAAAAUACGUAAAAUCACUCACUGCUUAGACACUACAUAAUCUAGUCCUUGGCUGCUUCUCUGACCCUGUCUUAUACCAGUCUGCAUUUACUACAGUCCAUCUAUACUGGCCUCUUUGAACUGUUCUUCAGAUAUGAUAAGCUUGUCCUUGCUAAAAGCUCUAACUGUUAUUUCUGCUUGGAAUGCUCUUCUCGUCUACUCUUCCUAUGCCUAGCAUUUUCUUAAUGUUUAGGUCUCACCUGAGAUGUCACUUUCACUGUAGUACUAGUAGUUGAUGUUACUACUGAUUCGUUGGCAGUAUUCCUGAAAUAGAAUAUAGGAUAAAUGAGGACAUGUUUAUUUUGUUCACAGCUGUGUCCACAAAAUCUAAACAGUGCCUGUAGUACUGUAGGAGCUCAUUAAGUAGUCGGCUGAUUGAUUUUUGUACCUAAUGGUUCUAUUAACAAUAUUGACCCCCAAAUGUAUUUUCUUCAUAACCUUCUCCUCUGAACUCCAGUCUGUAUAUUUAACUGUCUACCUGACAUUUCCACUUCUAAGCUUAAAAGCUCCUCCAAUUGAACCUGUGAUCUCUUUAAAUCUGGGACUCCAGGAUUUCCUGCCACAGUGAAUGGAUUUACCUUUUAUCUAUCUCUGUAAGCUAGAAAGUUGAGAGUCUUCUUCAAUGCCUUCUUUCCCCCUCAUAUUCAAUCCAUCAAAUGGAUUCUAUGGACUUUGCCACCUGAAUAUCUCUUGAAUCUGUUCCUACAUUUUAAACUACCAUCAUUUGAUGGAUUUUCACACAGUGAGUGUAUCUAUAUAAUUAAUACCCAGGUCAGGAAAUACGAUAUUACUAGCACCUUAGAAGCUCCUUGUGCCCUCUCUCUGUCAGAGUGAUCUUUUUAAAGGGAAAAUGUGAUCAUGCUUAAUGCCUUUCAGUUGCUUCCCAUUGCUCUUAGAAUAAAGACCAGAAAUCAUAAUGUGAUAUUUAAGAUCCUGGAUGAUGUUACUGUUUUUCCUAUGCAACUUCAUGUUUUUUAAAUUAUUUUUCUCACUUUCUGUAUUCCAGCCCUGAUAACCACCUCUCAAUUCCUUGAAUGUGGUAUGCUGUUCCCUCUUGCUAAAAAAUUCUAUGUACACAUACCCCUUCCGUUCUUGUCCUUCAGAUUUGAGCUCUUCAAAGUUUUCUUGGACAUAGCAAGCUUGAUGAGGUCCCAAAUACAUCUUAUGUGCUCUCAUAUGCUUUAUUCAUUUGUAUAUUAUUAUUUCCCUUAUUUUUAAGCUAAUGAGUCAGGUAUUACACCUGUUUUGCUCACUGUUGCUUGGUCAUCAGCUAGCAUGGUGGCUGGGAAAGAUUAGUAUUCAAUAUUCAUACAAUAAGUGAAUAUGAGUAGUUUGGGUUUGUUAUGGGAUGAAUUAUCCAUCCCCACCCCCCACUCCCACACACAGACACCCAACUGAUACACUGAAGAUUGAAAUUCUAACUGUAGAACCUAGAAUGUAACUGUAUUUGGAGAUGGGGCCUUUAAAAAGGUAAUGAAGAUAAAAUGAAGUCAUAUGGGUGGACUCCAAUUCCAUAUGAGUGGUUUCCAUUAAGAAGAGAUUAGGACACAGACACACAGAAAGGUAAGACCAUGUGAAGACACUGGAGGAAGAUGGCCAUCUACAAGCCAAAGAGAUCUACAGGCUUUAGAAGAAACCAACACUGCUGACACCUUGAUCUUGGACUUCUAGAAGUGUGAGAAAAUAAAUUUCUGUUCUUUAAACUACCCAAUCUGUGAUACUUUGCUAUGGAAGCCCUAGUAAACUUAUAUGGAUUUUGGUAUUGGGAAAGUGGGGUGCUGGUGUAAUUAAUACCUAAAAAUGUGGAAUUGGCUUUAGAACUAGAUAAUGGGUAGAGGCCAGAAGAAGUAUUUGUUAGAAAAAGCAUAGACUGCCUUGAAGAGAUUGUUGGUAGACAUAUGGAUGUUGAAGGUGAUUCUGGUGAAGCUUAGAAAAUAGGAGAGCUGUUGAGAAAGCUUCUGUCAUCUUAGAGGUAUACAUAUGUCACCUUGAAUAAAUAUUGGUAGAAAUAUGAAUGUUAAAGGUGUUUCUGGUAGGAACUCAAACAAAUGAGGAAUAUAUUGUUGGAAACUGAGGGAAAGGCAAUGCUUAUUAUAAUGUGGCAAAUAGCCAAAUUGUGUUUUGUGGAAAGUGGAUGAACUUACAAAGUGAUGAACUUGAAUGUUUAGCUGAGAUUUCUAAGCAAUGCAUUAAAGAUAUGGCCUGGUUUCUUCUUGCUGCUUAAAGUAAGAUGCAAGAGGAGAGAGAGAAAUUUAAGAAGGAAUUAUUAAGCCAAAAGCAACCAGAGCCUGAAGAUUCGGAAAAUUCUCAGUCUAUCCAUAUUGCAAAAAUUUAGCAUGUUCUGGAGGGAACAUCAAAGUUGUUGCAAGACAACCAUUUCCUAAAGCAAUUAGGGAUAUGUGACUUGUGGAUCCAAUCAGCCAUCUUGGCAGCAACUAGCAGAAGCCAGGAUAGAGAUGGGGUUAUACCUAUGGAAAUGCUGCUGGCUGGUACCGAAGGGAACAGAGGGAUAAAAAUGAAGGAAGUCUGUUGGAUUUCUUGAGAUUCUAUAAAAUGGGUCAGUAGAGCUAUCUGGCUGUGAACAUGUGUUCUUCAAGAAGAGGGAAGAAUGACCCUGAAGAUGAUUGAGAAGGCAAAGGGGCUACUAUUGCUACCACAGGACCAGAGGGCUCAGGCCUGAGGAGUCAAGGUAGGCUACUUCUUAGGGCUGAGGGAGGUGGGCUACCACACUGGUGGGCUCAGAAGACAGGGCUGCCACCCCUGUUAGGUGGGAAGAUGGAGAAUGAAGCUGAAGAAGAUUAUUCUUGAGCCUUAAAAUCUAAUGGGAUUUGCCUUUAUACGUUUCAGACCUGCUUAGGAUCCAUCACCCCUUCUUUCUGAUUUUUUUGGAAUAGGAAUGUUUAUCCUAUGCCUGUCUCACCAGUGGUGUAUUUUGGAAGCAAAUAACUUGUCUAGUUUCACAGGUUCAUGCUGGAGAAGAAUUUUGCCUCAGGGUGAAACCUUGAGUAUGCCUGUACCUGAUCUAAAUGAUAUUUAGAUGAGAUUUGGGGCUUAGAGUUGAUACUGAAAUGGGUCAAGACUUUGGGGCUGUUGGGAUGGAGUGGAUGUGUUUUGUGUCUGAGAAGGACAUGAAUUUUGAGGGGCCAGAUGGCAGAAUUUUAGAGGUUGAAUUGUAUGCUCUCCAAAUGUAUAUAAGUUAAAGUCCUAACUCCUAGUACCUAGAAUGUGACCAUAUUUGGAGAUGGGGCCUUUAAAAAGGUAAUUAAGAUAAAAUGACGUUAUACAUAUGAGCCCUAAUCCAAUAUGAAUGGUGUCUUUGUAAGAGGUUAGGACAAACACAAAGGGAAGAUCAUGUGAUGACACUGGAGAAAGAAGGCCAUCUACAAACUGAGGAGGGAGGCCUGAGAAGAGAUAAACCCUGUGGACAUCUUAAUCUUGGACAUCUAGCCUUCAGAAGUGUGGGAAAAUAAAUUUCUAUUGUUUAAGCCA